AGUUCUGCCGCGCACUGGGCCAGGGAGUGAUGAUUGCGUGGCUGACGGCUGGGCUGGUUAGUGUUUGCUGUUGCACGCUCUGGCGGUUCUCUCUGGAGUUGCUGCCUGAAAAGGCUCCCUUGUAAGACAGCCAAGAAAACAGGAAGAGGGUUGGAGGCAAAGUUCCGAAUAGGGAUGAGGCAUACGUGACAGGUAGAGCAGGUCUCUCUGCAGCCAUGUCGGCCAAGGCAAUUUCAGAGCAGACGGGCAAAGAACUCCUUUACAAGUUCAUCUGUACCACCUCAGCCAUCCAGAAUCGGUUCAAGUAUGCUCGGGUCACUCCUGACACAGACUGGGCCCGCUUGCUGCAGGACCACCCCUGGCUGCUCAGCCAGAACUUGGUAGUCAAGCCAGACCAGCUGAUCAAACGUCGUGGAAAACUUGGUCUCGUUGGGGUCAACCUCACUCUGGAUGGGGUCAAGUCCUGGCUGAAGCCACGGCUGGGACAGGAAGCCACAGUUGGCAAGGCCACAGGCUUCCUCAAGAACUUUCUGAUCGAGCCCUUCGUCCCCCACAGUCAGGCUGAGGAGUUCUAUGUCUGCAUCUAUGCCACCCGAGAAGGGGACUACGUCCUGUUCCACCACGAGGGGGGUGUGGACGUGGGUGAUGUGGACGCCAAGGCCCAGAAGCUGCUUGUUGGCGUGGAUGAGAAACUGAAUCCUGAGGACAUCAAAAAACACCUGUUGGUCCACGCCCCUGAAGACAAGAAAGAAAUUCUGGCCAGUUUUAUCUCCGGCCUCUUCAAUUUCUACGAGGACUUGUACUUCACCUACCUCGAGAUCAAUCCCCUUGUAGUGACCAAAGAUGGAGUCUAUGUCCUUGACUUGGCGGCCAAGGUGGACGCCACUGCCGACUACAUCUGCAAAGUGAAGUGGGGUGACAUCGAGUUCCCUCCCCCCUUCGGGCGGGAGGCAUAUCCAGAGGAAGCCUACAUUGCAGACCUCGAUGCCAAAAGUGGGGCAAGCCUGAAGCUGACCUUGCUGAACCCCAAAGGGAGGAUCUGGACCAUGGUGGCCGGGGGUGGCGCCUCUGUCGUGUACAGCGAUACCAUCUGUGAUCUAGGGGGUGUCAACGAGCUGGCAAACUAUGGGGAGUACUCAGGCGCCCCCAGCGAGCAGCAGACCUAUGACUAUGCCAAGACUAUCCUCUCCCUCAUGACCCGAGAGAAGCACCCAGAUGGCAAGAUCCUCAUCAUUGGAGGCAGCAUCGCAAACUUCACCAACGUGGCUGCCACGUUCAAGGGCAUCGUGAGAGCAAUUCGAGAUUACCAGGGCCCCCUGAAGGAGCACGAAGUCACAAUCUUUGUCCGAAGAGGUGGCCCCAACUAUCAGGAGGGCUUACGGGUGAUGGGAGAAGUCGGGAAGACCACUGGGAUCCCCAUCCAUGUCUUUGGCACAGAGACUCACAUGACGGCCAUUGUGGGCAUGGCCCUGGGCCACCGGCCCAUCCCCAACCAGCCACCCACAGCGGCCCACACUGCAAACUUCCUCCUCAACGCCAGCGGGAGCACAUCGACGCCAGCCCCCAGCAGGACAGCAUCUUUUUCUGAGUCCAGGGCCGAUGAGGUGGCGCCUGCAAAGAAGGCCAAGCCUGCCAUGCCACAAGAUUCAGUCCCAAGUCCAAGAUCCCUGCAAGGAAAGAGCACCACCCUCUUCAGCCGCCACACCAAGGCCAUUGUGUGGGGCAUGCAGACCCGGGCCGUGCAAGGCAUGCUGGACUUUGACUAUGUCUGCUCCCGAGACGAGCCCUCAGUGGCUGCCAUGGUCUACCCUUUCACUGGGGACCACAAGCAGAAGUUUUACUGGGGGCACAAAGAGAUCCUGAUCCCUGUCUUCAAGAACAUGGCUGAUGCCAUGAGGAAGCAUCCGGAGGUAGAUGUGCUCAUCAACUUUGCCUCUCUCCGCUCUGCCUAUGACAGCACCAUGGAGACCAUGAACUAUGCCCAGAUCCGGACCAUCGCCAUCAUAGCUGAAGGCAUCCCUGAGGCCCUCACGAGAAAGCUGAUCAAGAAGGCGGACCAGAAGGGAGUGACCAUCAUCGGACCUGCCACUGUUGGAGGCAUCAAGCCUGGGUGCUUUAAGAUUGGCAACACAGGUGGGAUGCUGGACAACAUCCUGGCCUCCAAACUGUACCGCCCAGGCAGCGUGGCCUAUGUCUCACGUUCCGGAGGCAUGUCCAACGAGCUCAACAAUAUCAUCUCUCGGACCACGGAUGGCGUCUAUGAGGGCGUGGCCAUUGGUGGGGACAGGUACCCGGGCUCCACAUUCAUGGAUCAUGUGUUACGCUAUCAGGACACUCCAGGAGUCAAAAUGAUUGUGGUUCUUGGAGAGAUUGGGGGCACUGAGGAAUAUAAGAUUUGCCGGGGCAUCAAGGAGGGCCGCCUCACUAAGCCCAUCGUCUGCUGGUGCAUCGGGACGUGUGCCACCAUGUUCUCCUCUGAGGUCCAGUUUGGCCAUGCUGGAGCUUGUGCCAACCAGGCUUCUGAAACUGCAGUAGCCAAGAACCAGGCUUUGAAGGAAGCAGGAGUGUUUGUGCCCCGGAGCUUUGAUGAGCUUGGAGAGAUCAUCCAGUCUGUAUACGAAGAUCUCGUGGCCAAUGGAGUCAUUGUACCUGCCCAGGAGGUGCCGCCCCCAACCGUGCCCAUGGACUACUCCUGGGCCAGGGAGCUUGGUUUGAUCCGCAAACCUGCCUCGUUCAUGACCAGCAUCUGCGAUGAGCGAGGACAGGAGCUCAUCUACGCGGGCAUGCCCAUCACUGAGGUCUUCAAGGAAGAGAUGGGCAUUGGCGGGGUCCUCGGCCUCCUCUGGUUCCAGAAAAGGUUGCCUAAGUACUCUUGCCAGUUCAUUGAGAUGUGUCUGAUGGUGACAGCUGAUCACGGGCCAGCCGUCUCUGGAGCCCACAACACCAUCAUUUGUGCGCGAGCUGGGAAAGACCUGGUCUCCAGCCUCACCUCGGGGCUGCUCACCAUCGGGGAUCGGUUUGGGGGUGCCUUGGAUGCAGCAGCCAAGAUGUUCAGUAAAGCCUUUGACAGUGGCAUUAUCCCCAUGGAGUUUGUGAACAAGAUGAAGAAGGAAGGGAAGCUGAUCAUGGGCAUUGGUCACCGAGUGAAGUCGAUAAACAACCCAGACAUGCGAGUGCAGAUCCUCAAAGAUUACGUCAGGCAGCACUUCCCUGCCACUCCUCUGCUCGAUUAUGCACUGGAAGUAGAGAAGAUUACCACCUCGAAGAAGCCAAAUCUUAUCCUGAAUGUAGAUGGUCUCAUCGGAGUCGCAUUUGUAGACAUGCUUAGAAACUGUGGGUCCUUUACUCGGGAGGAAGCUGAUGAAUAUAUUGACAUUGGAGCCCUCAAUGGCAUCUUUGUGCUGGGAAGGAGUAUGGGGUUCAUUGGACACUAUCUUGAUCAGAAGAGGCUGAAGCAGGGGCUGUAUCGUCAUCCGUGGGAUGAUAUUUCAUAUGUUCUUCCGGAACACAUGAGCAUGUAACAGAGCCAGGAACCCUACUGCAGUAAACUGAAGACAAGAUCUCUUCCCCCAAGAAAAAGUGUACAGACAGCUGGCAGUGGAGCCUGCUUUAUUUAGCAGGGGCCUGGAAUGUAAACAGCCACUGGGGUACAGGCACCGAAGACCAACAUCCACAGGCUAACACCCCUUCAGUCCACACAAAGAAGCUUCAUAUUUUUUUUAUAAGCAUAGAAAUAAAAACCAAGCCAAUAUUUGUGACUUUGCUCUGCUACCUGCUGUAUUUAUUAUAUGGAAGCAUCUAAGUACUGUCAGGAUGGGGUCUUCCUCAUUGUAGGGCGUUAGGAUGUUGCUUUCUUUUUCCAUUAGUUAAACAUUUUUUUCUCCUUUGGAGGAAGGGAAUGAAACAUUUAUGGCCUCAAGAUACUAUACAUUUAAAGCACCCCAAUGUCUCUCUUUUUUUUUUUUUACUUCCCUUUCUUCUUCCUUAUAUAACAUGAAGAACAUUGUAUUAAUCUGAUUUUUAAAGAUCUUUUUGUAUGUUACGUGUUAAGGGCUUGUUUGGUAUCCCACUGAAAUGUUCUGUGUUGCAGACCAGAGUCUGUUUAUGUCAGGGGGAUGGGGCCAUUGCAUCCUUAGCCAUUGUCACAAAAUAUGUGGAGUAGUAACUUAAUAUGUAAAGUUGUAACAUACAUACAUUUAAAAUGGAAAUGCAGAAAGCUGUGAAAUGUCUUGUGUCUUAUGUUCUCUGUAUUUAUGCAGCUGAUUUGUCUGUCUGUAACUGAAGUGUGGGUCCAAGGACUCCUAACUACUUUGCAUCUGUAAUCCACAAAGAUUCUGGGCAGCUGCCACCUCAGUCUCUUCUCUGUAUUAUCAUAGUCUGGUUUAAAUAAACUAUAUAGUAACAAUGAAGGCAU